UGGGUACACCCUCCUCACCCUGCUGGGUGGCAGGGCAGAGAGCACAGGCCUGUGCUGCUCUGUUGGCAUUAGGAGACUUUCUAGGAAUGCCAUUGUGCCCCCUUUCAACCUUGCUUGGGGAGAGGAUGUCCUCUCCUGCCAGGACUUCCUGGCCCCGGGACCCUCCCUUUGGAAGACGAAGUGCUGCCUGGGACCAGGUGGCCCAUGAGCCCCUGCCCGCACUGUGGGAGAUCUGCGCAUCUCUGGCAAGAGCCUCCAGGAGCCAUCUAAGGAGUUUAGUUUCCCCGGGGAGCUAUUCGGCCUUCCUGGUCUUUCCAGAUGAGUCAAAAGCAGCUGUUGAGACCUCUGAGUUGGGGGCCAGAAUGGAGGCCCAAGAGACCAAUGUUCUUUCUCCUGGGCCGGCUGCUUUGAGCAGCACUGGCAGCCUGGACUCAUUUGUCCUCAAUCCUCAACUCUGAGAGGCCCUCUUAUCUGUCUUAGGUGAUAUCGUUCUCAGGGUUCCUCCUGGGGCGAGGCACGCCAGGUCUGCUUGGCAACGCUGUUUUCCUCUGUCAGGAGCAGUUUGCAGAGAGAAAACUGGGGACAGGGCAGGAGACGGGCGUCCCCCAGCGGGGCCACCAGCACUGUUUGCCCUCCCCAGCCCUGGCUCCCUAGGAAUUCCAAGGAGACCCUCGCUCACUGUGCCCGUGGCCAUGGCUUUGCUCAGGUCCCUUUGGGGUGGCCUUCCCCACAGCCCUGCCUCUCAGAGGAAACUGGCUUUGAAUACUCACCCCUCUCUUCUUCCCAGGAACCACAGCGAAUUCUUGAGCUAGGAGAGGCUGCUCUGGGCGUGGGGACGAGGAGGCUGCAAGGCACCUGACUCUACCCUUCAGGAAUUCGGCAGAGACUGGAGCCUUCUCUCGAGACACCUGACUUAGUGUUCCCAGAGUUUGAUGAGAGGGACAUCUGGGCACAGGACCAUAUGACUGUAAUAAAUUAUAUAUAUGUAUAUAUACACACACACACACACACACACUUUUUUUUUUUUUUUUUUUUUGAGACGGAGUCUUACUCUGUGGCCCAGGUUGGAGUGCAAUGGCAUGAUUUCGGCUCACUGCAGUCUCCCCAGGUUCAAGUGAUUCUCCCACCUCAGCCUCCCCAGUAGCUGGGAUUACAGGUAGCUCCCCAGUAGCUGCUACCAUGCCCAGCUAAUUUUUUGUUUGUUUUGAGACGGAGACUUGCUCUGUUGCCCAGGCUGGAGUACAGUGGCGCGAUCUCAGCCCACUGCAAGCUCCGCCUCCUGGGUUCACACCAUUCUCCUGACUCAGGCUCCCGAGUAGCUGGGAUUACAGGCGCCCGCCACCACGCCCAGCUAAUUUUUUUCUUUGUUUUUUUGUUUUGAGUCUGAGUCUCGCUCUGUCGCCCAGGCAGCAGUGCAGUGGCAUGAUCUUGGCUCACUGCAACCUCUGCCUCCCGGGUUCAAGCAAUUCUCCUGCCUCGGCCUCCUGAGUAGCUGGGAUUACAGGUAUGCGCCACCACACCUGGCUAAUUUUUGUAUUUUUAGUAGCGGGGGGGUUUCCACCAUGUUGGUCAGGCUGGUCUCUAACUCCUGACCUCAUGUGAUCCACCUGCCUCGGCCUCCCAAAGUGCUGGGAUUACAGGCAUGAGCCGCUGCGCCCAGCCCUCUAGUAAAUAAUAUUAACAUUUAAUAUAAUUCUGGAAUUCUCUGGGGGUCCUGGAGCUUUGGUUAAAGGCAGGGUCCACAAGGGUAUUCCGAACAGGAUGCCAGGCAUGACGUCCACAGGGCCCUGGCCUUGGCCGGAGACUUGAGGACAGGAUGUUGGAUGUGAUCCUUAAACAAAGCAAAGAUGUCUGCCGUCGUUGAAAGUUGUUUCUAAAAGGUCUCCAGUGGGGGCUGCAGACUAAGCAAAAUGAGGCGGUUCCUGAGGCCAGGGCAUGACCCUGUGCGGGAGAGGCUCAAGCGGGACCUGUUCCAGUUUAACAAGACGGUGGAGCAUGGCUUCCCGCACCAGCCCAGCGCCCUCGGCUACAGCCCGUCCCUGCGCAUCCUGGCCAUCGGCACCCGUUCUGGAGCCAUCAAGCUCUACGGAGCCCCAGGCGUGGAGUUCAUGGGGCUGCACCAGGAGAACAACGCUGUGACGCAGAUCCACCUCCUGCCCGGCCAGUGCCAGCUGGUCACCCUGCUGGAUGACAACAGCCUGCACCUUUGGAGCCUGAAGGUCAAGGGCGGGGCAUCGGAGCUGCAGGAGGAUGAGAGCUUCACACUGCGUGGACCCCCAGGGGCUGCCCCCAGUGCCACACAGAUCACCGUGGUCCUGCCACAUUCCUCCUGCGAGCUGCUCUACCUGGGCACCGAGAGUGGCAACGUGUUUGUGGUGCAGCUGCCAGCUUUUCGUGCGCUGGAGGACCGGACCAUCAGCUCGGACGCGGUGCUGCAGCGGUUGCCAGAGGAGGCCCGCCACCGGCGUGUGUUCGAGAUGGUGGAGGCACUGCAGGAGCACCCUCGAGACCCCAACCAGAUCCUGAUCGGCUACAGCCGAGGCCUCGUUGUCAUCUGGGACCUACAGGGCAGCCGCGUGCUCUACCACUUCCUCAGCAGCCAGCAACUGGAGAACAUCUGGUGGCAGCGGGACGGCCGCCUGCUCGUCAGCUGUCACUCUGACGGCAGCUACUGCCAGUGGCCCGUGUCCAGCGAAGCCCAGCAACCAGAGCCCCUCCGCAGCCUCGUGCCUUACGGUCCCUUUCCUUGCAAAGCGAUUACCAGAAUCCUCUGGCUGACCACUAGGCAGGGGUUGCCCUUCACCAUCUUCCAGGGUGGCAUGCCACGGGCCAGCUACGGGGACCGCCACUGCAUCUCAGUGAUCCACGAUGGCCAGCAGACGGCCUUCGACUUCACCUCCCGUGUCAUCGGCUUCACUGUCCUCACAGAGGCAGACCCUGCAGCCACCUUUGACGACCCCUAUGCCCUGGUGGUGCUGGCUGAGGAGGAGCUGGUGGUGAUUGACCUGCAGACAGCAGGCUGGCCACCGGUCCAGCUGCCCUACCUGGCUUCUCUGCACUGUUCCGCCAUCACCUGCUCUCACCACGUCUCCAACAUCCCGCUGAAGCUGUGGGAGCGGAUCAUUGCCGCCGGCAGCCGGCAGAACGCACACUUCUCCACCAUGGAGUGGCCAAUUGAUGGUGGCACCAGCCUGACCCCAGCCCCACCCCAGAGGGACCUGCUGCUCACAGGGCACGAGGACGGCACGGUGCGGUUCUGGGAUGCCUCGGGUGUCUGCCUGCGGCUGCUCUACAAACUCAGCACUGUGCGCGUGUUCCUCACCGACACGGACCCCAACGAGAACUUCAGUGCCCAGGGCGAGGACGAGUGGCCCCCACUCCGCAAGGUGGGCUCCUUUGACCCCUACAGUGAUGACCCCCGGCUGGGCAUCCAGAAGAUCUUCCUCUGCAAGUACAGCGGCUACCUGGCUGUGGCAGGCACGGCAGGGCAGGUGCUGGUACUGGAACUGAAUGACGAGGCAGCGGAGCAGGCUGUGGAGCAGGUGGAGGCCGACCUGCUGCAGGACCAAGAGGGCUACCGCUGGAAGGGGCACGAGCGCCUGGCAGCCCGCUCAGGGCCCGUGCGCUUUGAGCCUGGCUUUCAGCCCUUCGUGUUGGUGCAGUGUCAGCCCCCGGCUGUGGUCACCUCCUUGGCCCUGCACUCUGAGUGGCGGCUCGUGGCCUUCGGCACCAGCCAUGGCUUUGGCCUCUUUGACCACCAGCAGCGGCGGCAGGUCUUUGUUAAGUGCACACUGCACCCCAGUGACCAGCUGGCCUUGGAGGGCCCACUCUCCCGCGUCAAGUCCCUCAAGAAGUCCUUGCGUCAGUCAUUCCGCCGGAUGCGUCGGAGCCGGGUGUCCAGCCGGAAGCGGCACCCGGCUGGCCCCCCAGGAGAGGCACAGGAGGGGAGUGCCAAGGCUGAGCGGCCAGGCCUCCAGAACAUGGAGCUGGCGCCUGUGCAGCGCAAGAUCGAGGCUCGCUCGGCAGAGGACUCCUUCACAGGCUUCGUCCGGACCCUGUACUUUGCUGACACCUACCUGAAGGACAGCUCCCGGCACUGCCCCUCGCUGUGGGCUGGCACCAAUGGGGGCACCAUCUAUGCCUUCUCCCUGCGUGUGCCUCCCGCCGAGCGGAGAAUGGAUGAGCCUGUGCGGGCAGAGCAGGCCAAGGAGAUCCAGCUGAUGCACCGGGCGCCGGUGGUGGGCAUCCUGGUGCUCGACGGACACAGCGUACCCCUUCCCGAGCCCCUCGAAGUGGCCCAUGAUCUGUCGAAGAGCCCUGACAUGCAGGGAAGCCACCAGCUGCUCGUCGUAUCAGAGGAGCAGUUCAAGGUGUUCACGCUGCCCAAGGUGAGUGCCAAGCUGAAGUUGAAGCUGACGGCCCUGGAGGGCUCAAGAGUGCGGCGGGUCAGCGUGGCCCACUUCGGCAGUCGUCGAGCCGAGGACUACGGGGAGCACCACCUGGCAGUCCUUACCAACCUGGGCGACAUCCAGGUGGUCUCGCUGCCCCUGCUCAAGCCCCAGGUGCGCUACAGCUGCAUCCGCCGGGAGGACGUCAGUGGCAUCGCCUCCUGCGUCUUCACCAAAUAUGGCCAAGGCUUCUACCUGAUCUCACCCUCGGAGUUUGAGCGCUUCUCUCUCUCCACCAAGUGGCUGGUGGAGCCCCGGUGUCUGGUGGAUUCAGCAGAAACCAAGAACCACCGCCCUGGUAACGGUGCGGGCCCCAAGAAGGCCCCGAGCCGAGCCAGGAACUCAGGGACUCAGAGUGAUGGCGAGGAGAAGCAGCCCGGCCUGGUGAUGGAGCGCGCUCUGCUCAGUGAUGAGAGAGCGGCAACUGGCGUUCACAUCGAGCCGCCGUGGGGUGCAGCCUCAGCAAUGGCGGAGAGUGAGUGGCUGAGCGUCCAGGCUGCGCGAUGAGCACACACUACUACUGAUGGCCUUUCGGGGGUCCCUGCCCCAACCGGAGAGGCCGGUGCACAGGGCCCCGCCAGGGGCUGGGGGCAUCCCGGCUUCCACAAUGCAGCUGCUCUGGGCCUCGGGAGAGGAGAGACCCCAGUCCCCUGGGCUGCCCUUCCCGGGCCUCGUCUGUCUGGGUCCUUUGGUCAAUGUUGCACAGUUUUUAUUGCUCCCAUCCCUUUUUGUAGUGGGCUGGGUUUUAAGUUAUAAAUGUUAACUGCCUCUGGGUGAAAAAGUUUUUAAUAAACACCUAUUACCUCUUGA